AGGACGGGGCGGAGCUUCCGCCUGGGCUGGGGUUGGCGAGUUCACCCGCGGCGGAGGGUAACUUUGCUGUGCUGUUUUUUGAGCAGUUGUCUGGUCCCUGGAAGUGUAGCAUCGAGAGAGUUUUCUAAUUACGUUUACAAAAUAUCUUCCCUUUGGCCAUACAAGUGGUGACUGCCAUGUCGAACUCGCGGCCCAGGUCCCGCCGAGACGCCGGGGGUGGCGCUGGGGCAGCCGGCCGGGACGAGCUGGUGUCGCGGUCCUUGCAGAGCGCAGAGCACUGUCUGGGCGUCCAGGACUUCGGCACUGCCUAUGCCCACUACCUCCUCGUGCUCAGCCUGGCGCCGGAGCUGAAACACGACGUGAAGAAUGGGCUUUAGGGAUGAAGCAGCUGGGUAUUUUCAUAAAGCAGUGAAGCUAAACCCUGAUUUCAGUGAUGCAAAGGAGAAUUUUUAUCGUGUUGCAAACUGGUUGGUGGAACGCUGGCACUUUAUCAUGCUUAAUGACACCAAGAGGAAUACAAUUUAUAAUGCAGCAAUCCAAAAGGCAGUUUGUUUGGGGUCCAAAAGUGUUUUGGACAUUGGAGCAGGAACUGGAAUACUAAGCAUGUUUGCUAAAAAAGCUGGAGCACAUUCCGUGUAUGCCUGUGAGUUAUCCAAGACCAUGUAUGAACUUGCCUGUGAUGUCGUGGCAGCAAACAAGAUGGAAGCAGGGAUCAAACUCUUACAUACGAAGUCACUUGACAUAGAGAUUCCAAAACAUAUUCCCGAAAGACCAAAGGUGAAAGUGCUAAUUGUGAAAAGUAUGGGAAAGUUAUACCAGCAAGUGCUGUUAUAUUUGGGAUGGCAGUAGAAUGUGCAGAGAUAAGAAGACAUCAUAGGCCCUGGUGACCACACAACAUCUUAACCAAGUGAUUAAAGCUAACAUCAACAGUAAGAUUGCUCCAGAUUUGAUGCUUUGAGGAUGCAUUGCUUAUAUAGUACCACAUCCAAAAUGUACAGCCUGCAAUCUAAUUGUGAGAAAACCUUGGACAAACCCUAGUUGGGACCAUUCUGUAAAACAAUUGGCCUACCUUCUUAAAAAAUGUCAGUGACAUGAGAGACAAAGCAAAGAUGAAGAACUGUUUAAGAUGAAAGGAGAUUAAAGAGACAGGACAGCUAAAUUGAAACUAUGACCUGUAUUGGGGAAAAAAACUAUAUAUGUAUAUUUUGAUCUUGCUGUGUUGCCCUGGUUGGAGCACAGUGGCUCAAUCAUGGCUCACUGCAGUCUUGACCUCCCAAGCUCAAGUGAUCCUCCUACUUCAGCCUCCUGAGGAGCUGCCAACCACAGAGUGGGUAUUAAGGACAUUGCUGGUAUCCAUUUGCCAACAAAUGUGAAAUUUCAGAGUCCGGCUUAUUCUUCUGUAGAUACUGAAGAAACAAUUGAACCUUAUACAACUGAAAAGAUGAGUCGAGUUCCUGGAGGAUAUUUGGCUUUGACAGAGUGCUUUGAAAUUAUGACAGUAGAUUUCAACAACCUUCAGGAAUUAAAAAGUCUUGCAACUAAAAAGCCUGAUAAGAUUGGUAUUCCUGUUAUUAAAGAAGGCAUACUAGAUGCUAUUAUGGUUUGGUUUGUGCUCCAGCUUGAUGAUGAACAUAGUUUAUCCACAAGUCCUAGUGAGGAAACAUGUUGGGAACAGGCUGUCUACCCCGUACAGGACCUUGCAGACUACUGGAUAAAGCCUGGAGACCAUGUGAUGAUGGAAGUAUCUUGUCAAGACUGUUACUUAAGAAUCCAGAGUAUUAGUGUCUUGGGUUUGGAAUGUGAAAUGGAUGUUGCAAAAAGUUUUACCCAGAAUAAAGACUUGUUAUCGUUAGGAAAUGAGGCUGAACUUUGUAGUGCCCUCGCUAACCUUCAGACCAGUAAACCAGAUGCUGUAGAGCAGACAUGUAUAUUGGAAUCUACAGAAAUUGCUUUGCUUAACAACAUCCCAUAUCAUGAAGGCUUUAAAAUGGCAAUGAGCAAAGUUUUGUCUUCACUGACUCCAGAGAAACUGUAUCAGACCAUGGAUACUCACUGUCAGAAUGAGAUGAGCUCUGGAACUGGACAGAGUAAUACUGUACAGAACAUCCUUGAACCUUUCUACGUGUUAGAUGUGUCCGAAGGCUUCUCUGUUCUGCCUGUUAUUGCUGGCACACUUGGGCAGGUUAAACCAUACAGUUCUGUGGAGAAAGACCAGCAUCGUAUUGCUCUGGACCUCAUAUCUGAAGCCAAUCACUUUCCUAAAGAAACACUUGAGUUUUGGCUGAGACAUGUGGAGGAUGAAUCUGCUAUGUUACAAAGGCCAAAAUCAGACAAGUUAUGGAGCAUAAUUAUAUUGGAUGUCAUUGAGCCAUCUGGGCUCAUUCAGCAGGAAAUAAUGGAAAAAGCUGCAAUAUCCAGGUGUUUACUACAAUCUGGAGGCAAGAUCUUUCCUCAGUAUGUGCUGAUGUUUGGGUUGCUUGUGGAAUCACAGACACUCCUAGAGGAGAAUGCUGUUCAAGGAACAGAACGUACUCUUGGAUUAAAUAUAGCACCUUUUAUUAACCAGUUUCAGGUACCUAUACGUGUAUUUUUGGACCUAUCCUCAUUGCCCUGUAUACCUUUAAGCAAGCCAGUGGAACUCUUAAGACUAGAUUUAAUGACUCCGUAUUUGAACACCUCUAACAGAGAAGUAAAGGUAUACGUUUGUAAAUCUGGAAGACUGACUGCUAUUCCAUUUUGGUAUCAUAUGUACCUUGAUGAAGAGAUUAGGUUGGAUACUUCAAGUGAAGCCUCCCACUGGAAACAAGCUGCAGUUGUUUUAGAUAAUCCCAUCCAGGUUGAAAUGGGAGAGGAACUUGUACUCAGCAUUCAGCAUCACAAAAGCAAUGUCAGCAUCACAGUAAAGCAAUGAAGAGCAGUUUUCCAAUGAAAACUGUGUAAAUAGAGCAUCAACAAGUACAAAAUUCUUGUCUUAAUUAGUGGGGGUAUAUAAAAAUUCCUUGUAAUGGUCAAAUAUUUUUUAAAAUUGACAUUAAUAAAGCAUAUUUUAAAAGAUUCUAAAUAAAAGGGUAGCAUUAUUAUAGAAAUACUGCUGCAGAUUUGCUUUCUGGAAAAGGAUACAUCACUAGUUUUUUAAAUUAGGAAACUUCUUUUGCUCGAUUUUACAGAAUAGGGAUUUUAAAAGUCUUAUCGUUAUUGACAUGUGUAAGUAAAGCAAAACUUUACUUUUGUAGGCAUCUUGGCCUUUUUUCUUAAAUCCAAACUUGUAAUUGGGAAACACUGAAAGGCUUCCACUGAAGACUGAGGGUUAUGGUUACCUGUAAAUUCCAAUCUUGCUUCCUUUAAAUACUCAGUGUACAUCUGAAACAUCUCAGGUUUUGUUUUGAGAAUGCAAGCUUGAAAAAGAAUUUAAGCUAUAAGCUAAAUGUAAUUAAAACAGUAAAGGAGUUAGGGAAUACAUCUUCAGGAGGCAGCAUUUUUCUUGGUCUACUUUGGCAAAAGAACAUUUAAAAGCUGGUAACAAAACAAAGUUAAAUUGAAGGAAGACUUAAUCCUAUACUAUUUUUCAAAGUUUUGAUUUGGAUGUACAAUAAGUACAUUAAUUGAUCCAAUUUUUACAAACUUUUGAAAUAAAGGAAGAUCAUUAUUAUGCCUCCUA